GAAGAGACGCUGCAGCUGCGGUGGCGGUGGCGGCCACUGCAGCUCAGAGCGGCGCACGCGGCGGCCGGGGCGGGACGCGGGGCCGGGCGCGGAGAAGUCGGGGCGGGCGGCAGAGAGGCCGGGACGCGGACCGGGCCGGGGCGCCCACAGCCGCCCGACGGCGCCCAGAGAGCGCGCGCCCCGCAGCCCCGCGCCUAGCCCGCCGGGCAUGGGGCGCGCGGCAGCCGCCUGAAGCCCCGGCCUGGCCCGGCCGCACCCGGCCGGAGGCGGAGGGCAGAGCGCGCGCCCAGUUGCCCGGGCACCAAAUCGGAGCGCGGCGUGCGGGAGGCCCCAGAGCAGGACUGGAAAUGUCCUGGCCGCGCCGCCUCCUGCUCAGAUACCUGUUCCCGGCCCUCCUGCUUCACGGGCUGGGAGAGGGUUCUGCCCUCCUUCAUCCAGACAGCAGGUCUCAUCCUAGGUCCUUAGAGAAAAGUGCCUGGAGGGCUUUUAAGGAGUCACAGUGCCAUCACAUGCUCAAACAUCUCCACAAUGGUGCAAGGAUCACAGUGCAGAUGCCACCUACAAUCGAGGGCCACUGGGUCUCCACAGGCUGUGAAGUAAGGUCAGGCCCAGAGUUCAUCACAAGGUCCUACAGAUUCUACCACAAUAACACCUUCAAGGCCUACCAAUUUUAUUAUGGCAGCAACCGGUGCACAAAUCCCACUUAUACUCUCAUCAUCCGGGGCAAGAUCCGCCUCCGCCAGGCCUCCUGGAUCAUCCGAGGGGGCACGGAAGCCGACUACCAGCUGCACAACGUCCAGGUGAUCUGCCACACAGAGGCGGUGGCCGAGAAGCUCGGCCAGCAGGUGAACCGCACAUGCCCGGGCUUCCUCGCAGACGGGGGUCCCUGGGUGCAGGACGUGGCCUAUGACCUCUGGCGAGAGGAGAACGGCUGUGAGUGCACCAAGGCCGUGAACUUUGCCAUGCAUGAACUUCAGCUCAUCCGGGUGGAGAAGCAGUACCUUCACCACAACCUCGACCACCUGGUCGAGGAGCUCUUCCUUGGUGACAUUCACACUGAUGCCACCCAGAGGAUGUUCUACCGGCCCUCCAGUUACCAGCCCCCUCUGCAGAAUGCCAAGAACCACGACCAUGCCUGCAUCGCCUGUCGGAUCAUCUAUCGGUCAGACGAGCACCACCCUCCCAUCCUGCCCCCAAAGGCAGACCUGACCAUCGGCCUGCACGGGGAGUGGGUGAGCCAGCGCUGUGAGGUGCGCCCCGAAGUCCUCUUCCUCACCCGCCACUUCAUCUUCCAUGACAACAACAACACCUGGGAGGGCCACUACUACCACUACUCAGACCCGGUGUGCAAGCACCCCACCUUCUCCAUCUACGCCCGGGGCCGCUACAGCCGCGGCGUCCUCUCGUCCAGGGUCAUGGGAGGCACCGAGUUCGUGUUCAAAGUGAAUCACAUGAAGGUCACCCCCAUGGAUGCGGCCACAGCCUCACUGCUCAACGUCUUCAACGGGAAUGAGUGCGGGGCCGAGGGCUCCUGGCAGGUGGGCAUCCAGCAGGAUGUGACCCACACCAAUGGCUGCGUGGCCCUGGGCAUCAAACUACCUCACACGGAGUACGAGAUCUUCAAAAUGGAACAGGAUGCCCGGGGGCGCUAUCUGCUGUUCAACGGUCAGAGGCCCAGCGACGGGUCCAGCCCAGACAGGCCAGAGAAGAGAGCCACGUCCUACCAGAUGCCCUUGGUCCAGUGUGCCUCCUCUUCGCCGAGGGCAGAGGACCUCGCAGAAGACAGUGGAAGCAGCCUGUAUGGCCGGGCCCCUGGGAGGCACACCUGGUCCCUGCUGCUGGCUGCACUUGCCUGCCUUGUCCCUCUGCUGCAUUGGAACAUCCGCAGAUAGAAGUUUUAGAAAGUUCUAUUUUUCCAAACCAGGAUUCCUUACUAUUGACAGAUUUGCUUUACCAAAAGAAAAGACAUUUAUUCUUUUGAUGCACUUGAAUGCCAGAGAACUGUCCUUCUUUUUCUCCUCUCCCUCCCUCCCAGCCCCUGAGUCAUGAACAGCAAGGAGUGUUUGAAGUUUCUGCUUUGAACUCCGUCCAGCCUGAUCCCUGGCCUGAGCAACUUCACAACAGUAAUUGCACUUUAAGACAGCCUAGAGUUCUGGACGAGCGUGUUUGGUAGCAGGGAUGAAAGCUAGGGCCUCUUAUUUUUUUCUCUUAAUUAUUAUUAUAUUUCUGAGUUAAACUUAGAAGAAACAACUAUCAAGCUACAACUUUUCCUGCCAUUUUCCUGUGGUUGCAGCCUGUCUUCCUUUGAAAUUGUUUUACUCUCUGAGUUUUAUAUGCUGGAAUCCAAUGCAGAGUUGGUUUGGGACUGUGAUCAAGACACCUUUUAUUAAUAAAGAAGAGACACAGGUGUAGAUAUGUAUAUACAAAAAGAUGUACGGUCUGGCCAAACCACCUUCCCAGCCUUUAUGCAAAAAAAGGGGAGAAUCAAAGCUUUCAUUUCAGAAAUGUUGCGUGGAAAAGUAUCUGUAAUUAAAGUUUCGAAGUAAUUUAACCUAUUUUUACAUCAUUUGUCUUACCUUGUUGAGAGAGGAGACUGGCUUGUUGGCUUCUGGUUGUUGCAGGAGGCAUGUGGCUUCCUGCCUUCUCAGUAGACAGGAUCAUUAGGAAAAUAGCAACAUCAAUCCUGUUACACAGGAGCAGUGACACGGGUGGCUGCAGUGUGGUACAUGCCACACAAAUGAUAGAGAAAGUGCCCGUUCAUUGCAGUUUCCUCUUCCUGGGGGACCUGAGCCCUGACUCACUGUCUUAUUAGGGGCAGGCGGAAGAAGCUGCACUCUGGCAUCCAUGCCACCUUCUAAGAUGAACAUGCAGAGACAGAACUUCAGCUGCUCAGAGAGAGUGCAGUGGGCAUGGUCUGCCCUGGGGGCUUGCUCCAUUACACCCUGACUUGGCAUGCAACCGAGUCUUUGUGUAAAGCCAUCCUGUCAUUGCACAUACUGGCUCACUCAGUGUCUUUCCUGCUGCUGAUGUGGCUCUGUGCUGGCAGUUUCAGGGUCAGUGUGCUGCUUUCCUAGGGACAUUAGAAGGGCGCAGGAGUGCAUGUCUGCCCAUUCCUUUGGAGUAUCGCAGAUGAUGCUAUACGAUACCAAGUGUUACCGCUCACAGAGACUGGGAAAGGGAAAUGGGAGUAACCGAAAGCCAGAUGGAACGAAAGCAAACAUGGAAACCAUGAUCACGGCAAAGAGCCAUCCUUGUAUUUAAGAAGUAACUUUGGCCAGGUGUGAUGGCUCACGCCGUAACCCCAGCACUUUGGGAGACCAAGGAGGGUGGAUCACGAGGUCAGGAGAUCAAGACCAUCCUGGCUAACACUGUGAAAUGCUGUCUCUACUAAAAAUACAAAAAAUUAGCCAGGCGUGGUGGUGGGCACCUGUAGUCCCAGCUACUCGGGAGGCUGAGGCAGGAGAAUGGCAUGAACCUGGGAGGUGGAGCUUGCAGUGAGCCGAGAUUGUGCCACUGCGCUCGAGCCUGGGCAACAGAGCGAGACUCCAUCUCAAAAAAAAAAAAAAGUAACUUUAUGAAAUGCCACAGCAUUCAGUGUGGCAUUAAGUUACAACGACCACAUAGAGUACCAAAGUGCUUCAGGUUAUAUUUUAAGUUGUGGUGCAGACUGAGGGGGCUUAUUCAAAAUGAAAAUACUAACUUAAAUGGCCACCAAGUUCAAUAAACAAAGAUGUCAAAAUACUCUCAGAAAUACAACUGAUACUAUCUUUAAAAGACGUAAUAAAAUCAUGUGAAAAACUGUA